AGACGGACGCACCGGCGAGCGCCGAGGGGACAGGCCGAGCGCGGGGCGCCGGAGGCAGCAGGACCCUCCCGAGGGCCUGACCGUGGAGGUAGCACUGCACACCCACUCCCUGUGGGCCGGAGCCAGGAGGCACUUCCUGGGUGUCGGAGCCCAGAAGGAAACCAGUGGCCGGGAAGCACCAGCUGGGUCAGUCUCCAGGUGUGGGACAGGCACUGGCCUCAGACCGGGGCCACACUGAGGUCUGCCCUUCUCCCGCUGGCCGCCACCCAAGACACCAUGAGCCAGUCCGGGGCCGUGAGCUGCUGCCCGGGUGCCACCAAUGGCAGCCUGGGCCGGUCCGACGGUGUGGCCAAGAUGAGCCCCAAGGACCUGUUUGAGCAGAGGAAGAAGUAUUCCAACUCCAACGUCAUCAUGCACGAGACCUCGCAGUACCACGUCCAGCACCUGGCCACAUUCAUCAUGGACAAGAGCGAAGCCAUCACGUCUGUGGACGACGCCAUCCGGAAGCUGGUGCAGCUGAGCUCCAAGGAGAAGAUCUGGACCCAGGAGAUGCUGCUGCAGGUGAACGACCAGUCGCUGCGGCUGCUGGACAUCGAGUCACAGGAGGAGCUGGAAGACUUCCCGCUGCCCACGGUGCAGCGCAGCCAGACGGUCCUCAACCAGCUGCGCUACCCGUCUGUGCUGCUGCUCGUGUGCCAGGACUCGGAGCAGAGCAAGCCGGAUGUCCACUUCUUCCACUGCGAUGAGGUGGAGGCAGAGCUGGUGCACGAGGACAUCGAGAGCGCGUUGGCCGACUGCCGGCUGGGCAAGAAGAUGCGGCCGCAGACCCUGAAGGGACACCAGGAGAAGAUUCGGCAGCGGCAGUCCAUCCUGCCUCCUCCCCAGGGCCCGGCGCCCAUCCCCUUCCAGCACCGCGGCGGGGAUUCCCCGGAGGCCAAGAAUCGCGUGGGCCCGCAGGUGCCACUCAGCGAGCCAGGUUUCCGCCGUCGGGAGUCGCAGGAGGAGCCGCGGGCCGUGCUGGCUCAGAAGAUAGAGAAGGAGACGCAAAUCCUCAACUGCGCCCUGGACGACAUCGAGUGGUUUGUGGCCCGGCUGCAGAAGGCAGCCGAGGCUUUCAAGCAGCUGAACCAGCGGAAAAAGGGGAAGAAGAAGGGCAAGAAGGCGCCAGCAGAGGGCGUCCUCACACUGCGGGCACGGCCCCCCUCUGAGGGCGAGUUCAUCGACUGCUUCCAGAAAAUCAAGCUGGCGAUUAACUUGCUGGCAAAGCUGCAGAAGCACAUCCAGAACCCCAGCGCCGCGGAGCUCGUGCACUUCCUCUUCGGGCCUCUGGACCUGAUCGUCAACACCUGCAGUGGCCCAGACAUCGCACGCUCCGUCUCCUGCCCACUGCUCUCCCGAGAUGCCGUGGACUUCCUGCGCGGCCACCUGGUCCCUAAGGAGAUGUCGCUGUGGGAGUCACUGGGAGAGAGCUGGAUGCGGCCCCGUUCCGAGUGGCCGCGGGAGCCACAGGUGCCCCUCUACGUGCCCAAGUUCCACAGCGGCUGGGAGCCUCCUGUGGAUGUGCUGCAGGAGGCCCCCUGGGAGGUGGAGGGGCUGGCGUCUGCCCCCAUCGAGGAGGUGAGUCCAGUGAGCCGACAGUCCAUAAGAAACUCCCAGAAGCACAGCCCCACUUCAGAGCCCACCCCCCCGGGGGAUGCCCUACCACCAGUCAGCUCCCCACAUACUCACAGGGGCUACCAGCCAACACCAGCCAUGGCCAAGUACGUCAAGAUCCUGUAUGACUUCACAGCCCGAAAUGCCAACGAGCUAUCGGUGCUCAAGGAUGAGGUCCUAGAGGUGCUGGAGGACGGCCGGCAGUGGUGGAAGCUGCGCAGCCGCAGCGGCCAGGCGGGGUACGUGCCCUGCAACAUCCUAGGCGAGGCGCGACCGGAGGACGCCGGCGCCCCGUUCGAGCAGGCCGGUCAGAAGUACUGGGGCCCCGCCAGCCCGACCCACAAGCUACCCCCAAGCUUCCCGGGGAACAAAGACGAGCUCAUGCAGCACAUGGACGAGGUCAACGACGAGCUCAUCCGGAAAAUCAGCAACAUCAGGGCGCAGCCACAGAGGCACUUCCGCGUGGAGCGCAGCCAGCCCGUGAGCCAGCCGCUCACCUACGAGUCGGGUCCGGACGAGGUCCGCGCCUGGCUGGAAGCCAAGGCCUUCAGCCCGCGGAUCGUGGAGAACCUGGGCAUCCUGACCGGGCCGCAGCUCUUCUCCCUCAACAAGGAGGAGCUGAAGAAAGUGUGCGGCGAGGAGGGCGUCCGCGUGUACAGCCAGCUCACCAUGCAGAAGGCCUUCCUGGAGAAGCAGCAAAGUGGGUCGGAGCUGGAAGAACUCAUGAACAAGUUUCAUUCCAUGAAUCAGAGGAGGGGGGAGGACAGCUAGGCCCAGCUGCCUUGGGCUGGGGCCUGCGGAGGGGAAGCCCACCCACAAUGCAUGGAGUAUUAUUUUUAUAUGUGUAUGUAUUUUGUAUCAAGGACACGGAGGGGGUGUGGUGCUGGCUAGAGGUCCCUGCCCCUGUCUGGAGGCACAACGCCCAUCCUUAGGCCAAACAGUACCCAAGGCCUCAGCCCACACCAAGACUAAUCUCAGCCAAACCUGCUGCUUGGUGGUGCCAGCCCCUUGUCCACCUUCUCUUGAGGCCACAGAACUCCCUGGGGCUGGGGCCUCUUUCUCUGGCCUCCCCUGUGCACCUGGGGGGUCCUGGCCCCUGUGAUGCUCCCCCAUCCCCACCCACUUCUACAUCCAUCCACACCCCAGGGUGAGCUGGAGCUCCAGGCUGGCCAGGCUGAACCUCGCACACACGCAGAGUUCUGCUCCCUGAGGGGGGCCCGGGAGGGGCUCCAGCAGGAGGCCGUGGGUGCCAUUCGGGGGAAAGUGGGGGAACGACACACACUUCACCUGCAAGGGCCGACAACGCAGGGGACACCGUGCCGGCUUCAGACACUCCCAGCGCCCACUCUUACAGGCCCAGGACUGGAGCUUUCUCUGGCCAAGUUUCAGGCCAAUGAUCCCCGCAUGGUGUUGGGGGUGCUGGUGUGUCUUGGUGCCUGGACUUGAGUCUCACCCUACAGAUGAGAGGUGGCUGAGGCACCAGGGCUAAGCAAUUAAACCAGUUAAGUCUCCCAGGA